GACAGCCCCGCGGAGUCCCUGGAGGCAGUUGCUUCCCUGAGGAGGGUCCGGCUGCGGCCAGGUAAGGAGCCUUCCGGCGGCCCGCUGGGUCGUGGUCCGCCCUGGAGGCAUCUUGGUAUCUGUUGCACGGAACCCCGCCUCCUGCGGGGACCCCCAGACCAGCUUCUUUUCUUGCAAAACGGUCUCUUUGUAAAUCCACUUUUUAAAACCACGUCUCCUUUCAACGACUGAAGUAUUUAUUCCACAAAUAUUUACUGAACACCUACUGCAAGAGUAUAAGAUGUAGGGGAGAGGCAGCUAUCCUAUCUUAGGCGGCAAUUCUAGGUUUCCCAGGAAACCUCUAAACCUCAGAAACCUCUGCUAGAGGGCUUCUCAACUGCUAAGUGUAAGGAAACUUUAAAAAAAAAUUAUAGAAUUAUAGCAUACCCAGAUAACAUUCAUGUAAUACCAAAGAUCAUAUUGUAAAUUAAAAUUUGAGAAAUUACAAAAAUUGUAAAGAAAUACUUAAGUCUAUGUUAUUUUGCGCUUCUUUCCCCCUGUAGUUUGGUACUCCUUUUAUUAAGAACUAGAAGGAUGGCCGUGUCCGUUCUGGCAUUUUGGACUUGGAUCUUUUAACUGGGAAAAAUAGUUAGCUGUGUUCUGUUUCAUAAUGAAACCAACUCUUCUGAAUAUUAGUUAAAUGUUUGCACAGUGUUUUUAUCUAGGAUAGCAACUCUUAAAAUACCUGAAGGAUUCUAGUUUUCAAUUAUUAUAGUUUAGCACUUCCAUUUUAACUUUAUCUUAGUUUAUUUCACCCGGAAUCAGAUCCUAAGACAAAACUUUGAAGGCAGGUUGUUUAUAUGAGACGUAAUCCCAGGAAACAGCAGCAGGGAGGGGAAGAAAACUAAUAAAGGAAAUAUUACCAGAGAAAUUUCUCUGUGGGCUGAAUUCACUAGGGAAUACUGGGAGGCAUGUCUCAGUUAUCCCCUCUUGAGGGGCAAGGAAGCUGGAGUAUUUAUUCGCCAACUUCCAUCAGUUAUUGGAUGAAGCCUGAUAGGGCAGAACAUUGAUGCCCUAGAACUUCCAGUCUACCCUGUGUUCAGGGAGAGUAGGUUCUGGCAGCCAGAGAAAGCCCUUAGGCAAAAAGUCGCACAUGCUAACAUUUUGGAAGUUGGGCUGGUCGUGCAUAGAAAAGGUGUAUGUCAAGUGGAUAUGGGGGAGGCACUAAUAGCAGCUGCUACAUUCCACCCUUUGCAGCACUCGUAUCCAUUCUUCCUCCACAUCAAGUUCACACCAUGCCACCCUAAUUCUUUAAGGUAGUGGCUAGUCUCAAUUUUUAAAAGAAAAGGACUUACAAAAAAAAAGAUUAAUGGGACAAGCUGCAGAAUCCACUACUGCAAUUAAUCUGAGGUCUCUAAUUGAUCAUCUCCUUCCUCUAACAUCAUUCUAGAUUUUCCUUACUCUUGGCCAACACUUCUGCUGGUCUGUGUUUGCCCAGUAGGAUAACAAGCUUUCAUCCCUGAGGAGCAUAAGCCCUUGGUUACUGUGUCAUUGUAAGGUUUUGGUUGCUGCAAUUACCCAUUCACUGGACAUGAAAGCAUCAAGAGCUGUCUCAGAGAAUCCCCUGAGUUCAAGAAAUGCAUCCCCUAUCCCACUUAUCUAGCAGUUUAUGGCCAUACCACCCUGAGCACCCCCAAUCUCAUCCAAUCACAUAGCAGCAACCCUAUCUCCAUCUGCCAGUGCAAUAACUCCUUAUGAGCUUUUGGAGUCAAAAAUGACCAGGUGGCAGCAGUAGUUUUAAGAUUUAAUGAAACCUUUACUGGGUCCCCUGAUAGAACCAUCUCUCCCCUCCACCAGACCCAGGACCUCUUGUCCAGAAGUGAGGUGCAAAUUUCCCAAGUCAAUCACUGAGAGUAUUAGUGAGAGGGGUCACUCCUACUUCCAGCCCUUGAUUCAAAGCAUGUUCCUCAUCUUGAAGUACAUUGUCUCAAUCCCACACAAUCCCAAGCUAGCGCCUUAGCUGUGCCUUUAAGAGACCAUUCCAACAUUCUGUCAAACCAGUAGCUUCUAGGUAAAGUGGUAUUGUAAAAAGGGUCCUCUGAUCCAAGGCAAUGGUAUAUGAGAUCUCAUGAAGAUAAAUGAGACAUACUCUAAACCUUUAGGUAGUGGUGCUGGCCAAGGCACUGCAGGUAGGAAAAACAAGCCCAUAUUAGGAGCAUUUGUCACUUGCCCCUUUAAAGGUGAAGGGGUCCUGUGUAAUCAAUUUGUCACUGAAUGAAUGUUUUGUCUCCUAAAGGGGUUGUACCAUAUUGAGGGCUCAAUAUGAACAGGUCUCAAUUUGUAAUCAAUUUGUCACUGAAUGAAUGUUUUGUCUCCUAAAGGGGUUGUACCGUAUUGAGGGCUUAAUAUGAACAGGUCUCUGCCAUGAACAGGUAGAACAUUCAGCAGCAGUAGUGUAGCUAAACCAGCCUGGUGAAAGGAGGCCUUGAUAUGAGCCCAUGCCUAUCCUUCAUCACCUUCAUCCCUGCCACCAUGCCUACUUCAUUUACAAACCCAUUAUGCAAGCAUUGAGGUGACCAGAAGCAAAGAUUGGCUCAUGUCUACUGGAUAAAUUAUCCUGUCCACCUGGUUUUUUCAGUGCCUCUUCUGAGGUGGAUGCUUUCUGAGAUACAAAUAUCUAUGUAUUUUACAUCCACUUACAUUAGUUUUCUAUGCUGCAUAGCAAAUUACUGCAAAUUUAGCAGCUUAAAACAACACACAUUUGUGAUCGCACGGUUUCCAUGGCCAGGAGCCCUGGCAUCACUCACCUGGGUCCUCUGCUCAGGGUUUUACAAGGCUGCAAUCUGGUGUUGGCUGAGAUGUGCUUCCAUCUGGAGACUUGACUAGGGAAGAAUCCACUCCCAAGCUGAUUCACAUUGUUGGCAAGCAUCAUCGUUUUGUGGUUGUAGGACUGAGGUCACUGUUUUCUUACCAGCUGUUGGCAGGGGCUGCACUCACAUGCCACCCACUCUUCCUCAUCACGUGGUCCUCUCACAACAUGGCAGCUUACUUCUUCCAAGCCAACAGAAAGUCUCCCUCCAGUCCCCUAAAAUGGAGUCUUAUACCAUGUAGCAUAUUCAUGAGACAGACAUUCUGUCACCUUUGCUCUAUUUAGAAGCAAGUUACAGACCCCACUCCCACUCAAAGGAAGAGGAUUAUGCAAGGGUGUGACUCACUGGAGGUCAGAUUAGGGUGUGUUUGCUACACCACCCUCAUAGGCCCAAUCACAUGCUUCUUCCCCAGAACUCUUUUUCUCUUACCUUCUGAUCUUGUACCUUCUAGGCCCUUGAUGAAACCAAUCCGCAUUGUCCUCCAAAUUGAGGGCCUAGGAAUACUGCUUAAAGCUCUGCCUGCCAGGAAGAUUUCCCCUAAUCACCAUUUUUCAGGGCCACUUGUGAGAGGAACUCAUGUCUGGAAGCAUUACAUUUACAGCUUUUACCAGUAUAUUGUGAUUCAUCCAUGAAUUUUGUUUUCAUUUUCUGUCAGCUCUUCUUAGGGAAUUCCACAUGAGGUGUGAGCUGAAAGAGACAUUGGUGCAUGAGACAGGUGACAUGGGCAUCUGGGCUGCUUAUUUUUGAAAUUUAUUUGUGCCCUGAAGACCUGUUUGAGCCUGAUCCCAUUGUUCCAUUUUUAUCAUUUAAUGGGUUGCUGCAGUGCCUGCCUGACUUUAGGACUUGACUUGUCUGACAUAACCAGCUCAUAGUGGAUACUUCCAGUUGCAUAGUCACUUGAUAUCCCAUGACCAGGCAUUCAUUCUCUACCAGAGCCCAAGAGCAUGCCAAGAGCUGUUUUUUGAAUGGGGAAUUAUUCUCUGCUGCAGACAGCAAGGAUCUACAGAGAGAGGCUCCUGUUGUGGCUUUCCUAAGACUCCAGAAGGUAUCCUUACAUACCACAGCAUUGUGGGACCUUUAGUAUUGUGGGAUCUAGCCAGAUGUAUGGCCCAGGAAGCAAAGCCUCUGGUACUACAACCUAAAACUACAGAGCUCUUUCUUGCUGUGUGCCCCACUCAAAAAUGACAGCUUUCCAUGUCACCCACUAAAUGGGUCAAAACAGUAUUCUUUAGUGCGCUUUAUGCUCUCUUUGAAAACUAAAGAGGCCUGCAAAAUACUGUGCCUCUUUUUUAGAGGUUGAAGGUACAAGGUACAGUAACUCAUCCUUUACCUUGGACAGAAUGUCCCAGACCACUGGCCUUUUAAAACUUUACCAAAGUAAUAAGACCUUCAAACUUUGUAGGUUUAUCUCUCACUUUAUACUUACUGCUCAUGUGUCUUUAUAAGGGGAUCCGGGACACUUGCAACUUCCUGCUCACUAGGUCUGAUAUUGUCAAUAUUGUGGAUCAAGACCCCUUUAUACUAUAUUGUCUCAAACAGCAGGAGAGUCCUUGGGUAAGACUGGAUGUUCACUGUCACUGCUCUAAGUGAAUACAAAUUGCUUCCGAUCCUCUUUCUUGAUAGGGAUUGAAAAGGAUGCACACAUUGCCAGAUCAUCAGCUGCGUAAAAAAUACAAGAGACUGUGUCUAUCUAGUAAAGAUCCCAUCUGCACAGCAGUUGCAACUGGGACUACCAGCUUGUUAAAUUUGCAGAAGUCUACCCUCAUCUGUUGUGCUCUGUCUAGCUUCUACAAAAGCAAGACUGGAGAAAUAAGCAGGAUUGUACAUCUUUUAAAUUGUGUAUUUUGUGUCAUGACUUCUCAAGAGAAGACAGAAGAGUAUCCUUUUGCAGAUAUAUUUGAUGAAGAUGAAACUGAAAGGAAUUUUUUGUUGUCCAAACCUGUUUGCUUUGUUGUAUUUGGGAAACCAGGUGUUGGGAAAACAACAUUAGCCCGUUACAUAACACAGGCAUGGAAAUGUAUUCGUGUUGAAGCUUUGCCAAUUUUAGAAGAACAGAUUGCUGCUGAAACCGAAUCAGGAGUUAUGUUGCAAUCAAUGUUGAUCAGCGGUCAAAGCAUUCCAGAUGAACUUGUCAUAAAGCUAAUGUUGGAGAAGCUCAACUCCCCAGAAGUCUGUCACUUUGGUUAUAUUAUCACUGAAAUACCAUCACUUUCACAGGAUGCCAUGACUACCUUACAGCAAAUAGAAUUAAUUAAAAACUUAAACCUGAAACCUGAUGUUAUAAUCAAUAUAAAGUGUCCUGACUAUGAUUUGUGCCAGAGAAUUUCUGGGCAAAGACAGCACAAUAAUACGGGAUACAUAUACAGUAGAGACCAGUGGGAUCCUGAAGUCAUUGAGAAUCAUAGGAAAAAGAAGAAAGAAGCCCAAAAGGACGGAAAAGGAGAAGAGGAAGAAGAGGAAGAAGAGCAAGAAGAAGAAGAGGCAUUUAUUGCCGAAAUGCAGAUGGUGGCUGAAAUUCUUCAUCAUCUAGUUCAGAGGCCUGAAGAUUAUUUGGAAAAUGUUGAAAACAUUGUUAAGCUUUAUAAGGAAACAAUUCUCCAAACUUUAGAAGAAGUAAUGGCUGAACACAAUCCCCAGUAUCUCAUUGAGCUAAAUGGAAAUAAACCAGCAGAGGAGCUCUUUAUGAUUGUUAUGGAUCGACUUAAAUAUCUGAACCUAAAAAGAGCAGCUAUUCUAACCAAACUUCAGGGUGCAGAGGAAGAAAUUAAUGACACAAUGGAAAAUGAUGAGCUAUUUCGUACUCUUGCAUCUUAUAAACUUAUUGCACCAAGAUACAGAUGGCAAAGAAGUAAAUGGGGACGUACAUGUCCUGUGAAUUUAAAAGAUGGUAACAUUUAUUCAGGAUUACCAGAUUAUUCUGUGAGUUUUCUAGGUAAAAUCUACUGUCUUUCAUCAGAAGAAGCAUUAAAACCAUUUUUGUUGAACCCACGUCCCUAUCUGCUUCCACCUAUGCCAGGACCACCAUGUAAAGUAUUCAUACUUGGACCUCAAUAUUCAGGGAAAACAACACUUUGCAAUAUGCUUGCAGAAAAUUACAAAGGAAAGGUAGUCGACUAUGCCCAACUUGUUCAGCCACGUUUUGAUAAAGCCCGUGAAACAUUAGUAGAAAAUACCAUAGCUGAGGCCACUGCAGCAGCAAUUAAAGUUGUGAAAGAAAAGCUUCUCAGGGAACUGCAAGCUAGAAAACAAGCUGAAACAGCUUUAAGAGAAUUUCAAAGGCAAUAUGAAAAAAUGGAGUUUGGAGUAUUCCCAAUGGAGGCAACACACUCAUCAAUUGAUGAAGAAGGGUACAUUCAAGGCUCCCAAAGGGACAGAGGCAGCUCUUUAGUGGACACCGAAGAAGCCAAAACAAAGUCAGAAAAUGUCCUCCAUGAUCAAGCUGCUAAAGUUGAUAAAGAUGAUGGAAAAGAAACUGGUGAAACAUUCACAUUUAAAAGGCAUUCUCAAGAUGCUAGUCAAGAUGUAAAGUUGUAUUCAGAUACAGCCCCAACAGAAGACUUGAUAGAAGAGGUAACUGCAGAUCAUCCAGAGGUUGUGACCAUGAUUGAAGAGACUAUAAAAAUGUCACAGGAUAUAAACUUUGAACAGCCAUAUGAAAAACAUGCUGAAAUCUUACAGGAAGUCCUUGGAGAGGUAAUGGAAGAAAACAAGGAUAGGUUUCCUGGUGCCCCAAAAUAUGGAGGCUGGAUUGUGGACAACUGCCCUAUUGUAAAAGAAUUGUGGAUGGCCUUAAUCAAGAAAGGAAUUAUACCUGAUUUGGUCAUCUAUUUAUCAGAUACAGAAAACAAUGGAAAAUGUUUAUUUAAUAGAAUAUAUUUACAGAAGAAAUCUGAAAUUGACUCUAAGAUUUUAGAAAGAUUAUUAGAAGAACUACAAAAGAAAAAAAAAGAAGAAGAAGAAGCAAGAAAAGCCACAGAAGAGGAAUUGAGACUCGAAGAAGAAAAUCGAAGGCUACUGGAACUUAUGAAAGUGAAGGCAAAAGAAGCUGAAGAGACUGAUAAUGAGGAUGAAGAGGAGAUUGAAGGUGAUGAGUUGGAAGUUCACGAAGAGCCUGAGGCAUCUCACGAUACCCGAGGGUCAUGGUUACCUGAGGAGUUUGAAGCAUCUGAGGUCCCUGAAACUGAGCCUGAAGCAGUAUCUGAGCCUAUCGAGGAAACUACAGUGGAAACAGAAAUCCCAAAAGGAUCCAAAGAGGGCCUGGAAAUUGAAAAAUUAUCUGAAACAGUUGUACUACCUGAGUUUCCAGAAGACUCUUAUCCUGAUGUUCCCGAAAUGGAGCCAUUUAAAGAGAAGAUUGGUUCUUUCAUCAUCCUCUGGAAACAGCUAGAAGCAACAAUUAGUGAGGCUUACAUUAAAAUUUUAAACUUGGAGAUUGCUGACAGAACUCCACAGGAAUUACUUCAAAAAGUAGUUGAGACUAUGGAAAAACCAUUUCAAUAUACUGCAUGGGAGUUAACUGGGGAAGAUUAUGAGGAAGAAACAGAAGACUACCAGACUGAAGCAGAGGUUGAUGAGGAGCUAGAGGAAGAGGAAGAGGAAGAGGGUGAAGAUAAAAUGAAGGAGAGAAAGAGGCAUUUGGGAGACACAAAACACUUUUGUCCGGUGGUCCUCAAAGAAAACUUCAUCCUGCAACCAGGAAACACAGAAGAAGCAGCCAAGUAUCGAGAAAAGAUCUACUACUUUUCAAGUGCUGAGGCUAAAGAAAAGUUUUUGGAGCAUCCUGAGGAUUAUGUGGCUCAUGAAGAACCAUUGAAGGCUCCUCCAUUAAGAAUAUGCCUUGUCGGCCCCCAGGGCUCUGGCAAAACUAUGUGUGGAAGACAGUUGGCAGAAAAAUUAAACAUUUUUCACAUUCAGUUUGAAGAAGUUCUUCAAGAAAAACUACUACUCAAAACUGAAAAGAAAGUGGGACCUGAAUUUGAGGAAGAUUCUGAGAACGAGCAAGCUGCCAAACAAGAACUUGAAGAGCUUGCAAUUCAGGCCAAUGUCAAAGUUGAGGAAGAAAAUACAAAAAAGCAGCUUCCAGAAGUACAACUUACAGAAGAAGAAGAAGUAAUCAAAUCAAGUCUAAUGGAAAAUGAGCCCUUGCCUCCUGAAAUUCUUGAAGUAAUUCUUUCUGAGUGGUGGCUUAAGGAACCAAUACGUUCCACAGGUUUUAUAUUAGAUGGUUUCCCACGAUAUCCAGAAGAGGCCCAGUUUUUGGGAGAUCGUGGAUUUUUCCCAGAUGCAGCUGUUUUUAUACAAGUUGAUGAUCAAGAUAUUUUUGAUCGCCUCCUUCCUGCCCAAAUUGAAAAGUGGAAACUAAAACAAAAGAAGAAAUUAGAAAGGAAGAAACUGAUCAAAGACAUGAAGGCAAAAAUCAGGGUUGAUACGAUUGCUAAAAGAAGGGCUGAACUUAUAUUAGAGAGAGAUAAAAAAAGGAGGGAGAAUGUUGUUAGAGAUGAUGAAGAGAUUAGUGAGGAAGAACUUGAAGAAGACAAUGAUGAUAUUGAAAACAUCCUUGAAGAUGAGUUUCCAAAAGAUGAGGAAGAGAUGAGUGGCGAGGAAGAUGAAGAACAGGAAACUGAUGCAAUUGAGCGCCUGAGAGGUGAACUAGGAGAAAAAUUUGAAGCAGAUACACAUAAUUUACAAAUAAUACAGGAUGAACUUGAGAGGUAUUUGAUACCAAUAAUUUCCAUUAAUGGAGCUCGGAGAAAUCACAUUGUACAAUAUACAUUGAAUAUGAAACUGAAACCACUGGUGGAAAAUCGUGCAAGCAUUUUUGAGAAAUGUCAUCCAAUACCAGCACCCCUUGCCCAGAAAAUGCUCACCUUUACCUACAAGUAUAUAAGCUCAUUCGGCUAUUGGGACCCUGUAAAGCUAAGUGAAGGAGAGACAAUCAAGCCAGUUGAAAAUGCAGAGAAUCCAAUUUAUCCUGUAAUCCAUCGUCAGUAUAUUUAUUUUUUAUCUAGUAAAGAAACAAAAGAAAAAUUUAUGAAGAACCCAAUCAAAUAUAUCCGCCAACCCAAACCUAAGCCUACUGUGCCCAUUAGGAUUAUAAUUGUGGGGCCUCCAAAAUCUGGGAAAACUACAGUUUUAUGUUUUUCAGUUGCCAAAAAAAUUACAAGUGAAUAUGGGUUAAAGCAUUUAUCAAUAGGAGGAGCUUUGCGUUAUGUACUAAACAAUCACCCGGAAACAGAGCUGGCACUUAUGUUAAAUUGGCAUCUUCAUAAAGGAAUGACAGCACCUGAUGAACUGGCUAUUCAAGCCUUAGAACUUUCUCUGAUGGAAAGUGUGUGCAAUACUGCAGGUGUUGUCAUCGAUGGAUAUCCUGUAACUAAACAUCAAAUGAAUCUCUUGGAAGCUAGGUCAAUCAUUCCCAUGGUCAUCUUUGAAUUGAGUGUGCCUUCCAAGGAGAUUUUCAAAAGAUUGCUCCUAGAAAAAGAAAAUGAACAAAGAUUGCCUUAUCCAUUGCACAAUAGUGCACAAAUUGUAGCUGUCAAUAAUGUAAAGUAUCGCAAAAAUAUUGGUGAGAUUAGGCAAUAUUAUCAAGAACAGCAUCAGAACUGGUAUGUGAUUGAUGGAUUUCACAGCAAAUGGUGGGUAUGGAAUGAAGUCAUUAAGAAUGUUCAAAUGGUGAAUAAAUACAUGCAGACAUACCUGGAAAGAAUAAAAGCAGGAAAAGCUGCCUGCAUUGACAAGUUAUGUAUCACACCUCAAGAGCUGCUUUCUCGCCUGGGAGAAUUUGAACAGUUCUGCCCUGUCAGCCUGGCAGAAUCCCAGGAAUUAUUUGAUUGCUCUGCAACUGACUCCUUGGAAUUUGCAGCAGAGUUCAGGGGGCACUACUAUAAAAUGAGUUCUCAGGAAAAACUGAAUAAAUUCUUGGAGAACCCAGAAUUGUACGUGCCUCCCUUAGCACCUCAUCCACUCCCAUCUGCUGACAUGAUCCCCAAAAGACUGACACUGUCAGAGCUGAAGAGUCGAUUCCCUAAGUGUGCGGAGCUCCAGGGCUACUGUCCAGUGACCUAUAAGGAUGGAAACCAAAGAUAUGAAGCUCUAGUACCUGGUAGCAUUAACUAUGCUUUAGAAUAUCAUAAUCGUAUAUAUAUUUGUGAGAACAAAGAAAAACUCCAGAAAUUUUUGAGGUCGCCACUGAAAUACUGGGAACAGAAGCUUCCACACAAGCUUCCCCCAUUAAGGGAACCGAUACUUCUUACUAGUCUUCCUUUGCCUGGAUAUCUGGAACAGGGUAUUGCAACUUCUCUAAUUAAAGCAAUGAAUGCAGCGGGAUGCUUAAAGCCCAAGUUCCCCUUUUUAAGUAUAAGGAGAUCUGCACUGCUAUAUAUAGCACUUCAUCUCAAAGCAUUUAAUCCCAAAGGUUCCGAAUACACAAGAAAAAAGUAUAAGAAGAAGAUGGAGCAGUUUAUGGAGAGUUGUGAACUCAUAACAUACUUGGGUGCCAAGAUGACCAGAAAAUACAAGGAACCUCAGUUCAGAGCCAUUGACUUUGAUCAUAAGUUAAAGACCUUUCUCUCUCUCAGAAAUAUAGACCCAAUUAAUGGGUAGUUUACUUAGGUGAUAGCAGCCUGAAUCUCAAGAGUUAUCUGAAAGUGAUAGAGGGAAACUGAGAGAAGUAGAUUGAAAAUCUGGGCCUCUUGGAAGUACUUUUGCCUCCUGAGCAAGGUACCAUGGCUGCCAGACUUCAGGUGAACUCAAAGGUCUGCCAGCCAGGAAGGAGCACUCUUAUGGAAACAAGUUUUAAUACAAUUUUAAAAUGUAUUGCUCUUUGCCUGAACUUUGAUGCUUUAACAAAAUAAACAUUCUAUUUAUAAUUCCAUAUAGAAAAGUUAAGUGACUUAUUUAAUAAAUGUAUUAUUUUCCUUUUUAACAUUUUCAGUAGAAAAGUCAGUCUCUGUUAAAAUUACUCAUUAAAUGUUAGAAAGCUUUAAGACAUUUAACAUUGUUAUAAAUGAAACCAAAAUAUGGGUUAUACAUUUUACAUACAAAACUGUUUGUGAACUUUGUGAACAUAAGAUACUAUCAUUUUCCCAAUAAAAUAAAUGGAUUUUGCAACAACUUA